ACUUCCGGCGCGUUGGGGCUGUUGGUCGGGGGCGGCCGCGCGGUACUAGCGGGCGGCUCCAGGGCGGGCGCGCGCAAGGAUGCUCUAGGGGGCGGCGGCAGUGGCCGUGUGGGUUGAGGCUGCGAGGACAGCGCGGGCCCCCGGGCCUCUCCCCUGAGCCGGCCGCCUGGGCCGCGCGGUCGAGGCCUGUCAGCCUCCGCCCGUUCAGCCUCGGGGCCGGGGCCGCCGCCACCUCUGCCCGCGGAGGCCGGGGAGCCCCUGCCUGGGCCCGCAGCCUCCCCCGCGGGGGUCGGGCCCGGGCGGGGGUCCCGAGCAGCUGCCCUCCUCGCCGGCAUCCGAGCCUCAUUUCCUGCUUUUUCAGUUUCCUUGGGGAGGGGCGGGUGGGUCUGGAUGAAUUGUCUCGGGGUCCCCCGAUGAGGCGACCCGGGCGGCCCUGCCCUUUUUAGAGGGUCCCCUCGGGGCCCGGUGGGGAAGGGGUUGUCUUUGCAUGGGUGGGGGACUUCCCGAGUCUGCCGGGACCAUGACCUGAACUGUGCGAGCGGGACGUGUCCGAAGCCCAAGAACCAGCUCAUCUGAGCCGCCCCCUCCCCGGCCAGCAUGGUAGCUCAUGUAAGUGGAGUCAUGAAGUAUUUGGCCUGUUGUGACUGCCUUAUUUCACAUGGCACAGUGUUCUCAAGCUUCAUCCGUGUGGUGGCGUGUGUCAGAGCUUCCUUCCUUUUGAAAGCUGAAUUCCAUUGCAUCUGAAGAAGCCUCUCUCAGGGCAUUGGAAAGUCUGAUGACAGAAUUUUUUCACGAUUGUACAACCAAUGAAAGAAAACGUGAGAUAGAGGAGCUUCUUAAUAACUUUGCCCAGCAAAUAGGAGCCUGGAGAUUCUGCCUGUACUUUCUCUCCAGCACUAGGAAUGACUAUGUAAUGAUGUACAGUUUAACAGUUUUUGAGAAUCUGAUCAAUAAAAUGUGGCUUGGGGUCCCAUCUCAGGAUAAGAUGGAAAUCCGUAGCUGUCUGCCCAAACUCCUUUUGGCUCACCAUAAAACCUUACCUUACUUUAUCCGGAACAAGCUCUGCAAAGUUAUUGUUGAUAUUGGACGUCAGGAUUGGCCCAUGUUCUACCACGACUUUUUUACUAACAUUUUACAGUUGAUCCAGUCCCCUGUGACAACCCCCCUUGGGCUGAUCAUGUUGAAGACAACUUCAGAAGAGCUGGCUUGUCCCCGUGAGGACCUCAGUGUGGCUCGGAAGGAGGAGUUGCGGAAGCUGCUACUGGACCAGGUGCAGACAGUGCUUGGGCUACUGACAGGUAUCUUGGAGACUGUCUGGGACAAACACAGUGUUACUGCUGCCACUCCACCACCAUCCCCGACCUCAGGAGAAAGUGGUGACUUACUGAGUAACCUGUUGCAGAGUCCCAGUUCAGCCAAACUGUUGAAUCAGCCAAUUCCCAUCCUUGAUGUGGAGAGUGAGUAUAUCUGUUCCCUGGCUUUGGAGUGCCUGGCCCAUCUCUUCAGUUGGAUUCCUCUGUCUGCCAGCAUCACCCCAUCCCUCCUUACCACCAUCUUCCACUUUGCACGAUUUGGCUGUGACAUCCGGGCCAGAAAGAUGGCGUCAGUUAACGGCAGCAGCCAGAACUGUGUCUCGGGUCAGGAGCGCGGCCGGCUGGGGGUCCUGGCCAUGUCCUGCAUCAAUGAACUCAUGUCCAAGAACUGUGUGCCUAUGGAAUUUGAGGAGUAUUUACUGCGUAUGUUCCAGCAGACUUUCUACCUCCUGCAGAAAAUCACCAAGGAUAACAAUGCCCACACAGUGAAGAGCAGGCUAGAAGAGCUCGAUGAGAGCUAUAUCGAGAAGUUUACUGACUUUCUUCGGCUCUUUGUGAGUGUUCACCUAAGAAGAAUCGAGUCUUACUCCCAGUUCCCUGUGGUGGAGUUUUUGACACUUUUGUUCAAGUACACAUUUCAUCAGCCUACUCAUGAAGGUUACUUCUCUUGUUUGGAUAUCUGGACGCUGUUUUUGGACUAUCUGACAAGUAAAAUUAAAAGUCGUCUUGGAGACAAGGAAGCAGUUCUCAACAGGUACGAAGAUGCCCUGGUGCUCCUGCUCACAGAGGUGUUGAAUCGAAUCCAGUUCAGAUACAACCAAGCCCAGCUGGAGGAGUUGGAUGAUGAGACUCUGGAUGACGAUCAGCAGACGGAGUGGCAGCGGUACUUACGGCAGAGCUUGGAGGUGGUGGCCAAAGUGAUGGAGCUCCUGCCCACGCACGCCUUCUCCACACUGUUCCCUGUUCUUCAGGACAAUUUAGAAGUUUAUUUGGGAUUACAACAGUUUAUAGUCACUUCAGGGUCAGGACACAGGUUGAACAUCACGGCGGAGAACGACUGCCGGCGGCUGCACUGCUCCCUGAGAGACUUGAGCUCCCUGCUGCAGGCCGUGGGCCGCCUGGCCGAGUACUUUAUCGGGGAUGUGUUUGCUGCACGGUUCAAUGAUGCCCUCACAGUCGUGGAAAGGUUGGUCAAAGUCACUCUGUACGGAUCUCAGAUAAAAUUGUACAACAUUGAAACUGCUGUGCCAUCAGUAUUGAAACCUGACCUCAUUGAUGUGCAUGCUCAGUCCCUGGCUGCGCUGCAGGCUUACUCUCACUGGUUAGCACAGUAUUGCAGUGAAGUUCACCGGCAGAACACGCAGCAGUUCGUGACACUCAUCUCUACUACCAUGGAUGCAAUCACACCUCUAAUCAGCACCAAGGUCCAAGACAAGCUGCUGCUAUCUGCGUGCCACUUACUGGUCUCACUGGCCACCACCGUGCGGCCCGUCUUUCUGAUCAGCAUCCCUGCAGUGCAGAAAGUAUUCAACAGAAUCACUGAUGCCUCUGCCCUGCGACUUGUCGAUAAGGCCCAGGUGUUGGUGUGCCGAGCCCUCUCUAACAUCUUGCUGCUUCCGUGGCCAAACCUUCCAGAGAAUGAGCAGCAGUGGCCCGUGCGCUCCAUCAACCACGCCAGCCUCAUCUCUGCACUCUCCCGGGACUAUCGCAACCUGAAGCCCAGUGCUGUUGCCCCACAGAGAAAGAUGCCACUGGAUGACACCAAACUGAUUAUCCACCAGACACUCAGCGUCUUAGAAGAUAUUGUGGAGAAUAUCUCGGGGGAGUCCACCAAGUCUCGACAGAUUUGCUACCAGUCGCUGCAGGAAUCUGUUCAGGUCUCCCUGGCCCUCUUUCCAGCUUUUAUCCAUCAGUCAGAUGUGACUGAUGAGAUGCUGAGCUUCUUCCUCACUCUGUUUCGAGGCCUUAGAGUACAGAUGGGUGUGCCUUUCACUGAGCAAAUCAUACAGACUUUCCUCAACAUGUUUACCAGAGAGCAGUUAGCCGAGAGCAUCCUCCACGAGGGCAGCACAGGCUGCCGGGUGGUGGAGAAGUUUCUGAAGAUCCUGCAGGUGGUGGUCCAGGAGCCAGGCCAGGUGUUCAAGCCCUUCCUCCCCAGCAUCAUCGCCCUGUGCAUGGAGCAAGUGUAUCCCAUCAUUGCCGAGCGUCCCUCCCCUGAUGUGAAGGCCGAGCUGUUUGAGCUCCUUUUCCGGACGCUCCAUCACAACUGGAGGUACUUCUUCAAGUCCACCGUGCUGGCCAGUGUCCAGAGGGGGAUCGCUGAGGAGCAGAUGGAGAAUGAGCCCCAGUUCAGUGCCAUCAUGCAGGCUUUCGGACAGUCCUUUCUCCAGCCCGACAUCCACCUUUUUAAACAAAAUCUCUUCUACUUGGAGACUCUCAACACCAAGCAGAAGCUGUACCACAAGAAGAUCUUCCGGACUGCCAUGCUGUUCCAGUUUGUGAACGUGCUGCUCCAGGUCCUGGUCCACAAGUCCCAUGAUCUUCUGCAGGAGGAGAUUGGCAUCGCCAUCUACAACAUGGCCUCAGUCGACUUUGAUGGCUUCUUUGCCGCCUUCCUCCCAGAGUUCCUGACCAGCUGUGAUGGUGUGGAUGCCAACCAGAAAAGUGUGCUGGGGCGGAAUUUCAAGAUGGAUCGGGACCUGCCCUCAUUCACCCAGAAUGUGCACAGGCUGGUCAACGACCUGCGCUACUACAGACUCUGCAACGACAGCCUGCCCCCUGGCACUGUGAAGCUCUAGGCCUGCUACUGCCUGGGGACACGGACUUCUGCUGCUGCCACCUGCGCCAGCCCUACCUUCCACCACAGAUGUCUCCCAGAUGGGCCUUGGUCACACUCCUUGGCUUCUCCCACCGCAAGCAACGCUGCCUGCCUCUGCCGCUCCUCCACAUCUUGCCGCUGCCCAGCAGAGCUGGCUUCUGGGUCCACCUGAGCACUGGACGGUGCUCCCAGGGCGUUGGAGCAGGCGGAGGGGUGUGUGGCCAGGUACUAGGAGGCACCAGGAAAUCCCGCGGGGUGGCCCAUGCAGACCAGGCGCACGUGGCUCAUGGGGCAGAAUUGCCAAGGACAGCUCACGACAGUGCCACCUUCUCACCAUUCCAGCCAAGGAGAGAUGUGACGUUGGAACUGCUCUGGCACUUCUGUCAAGCCUCCCCCGCCCCAAUUGCCUUGAGAUCUCUGCUCUUUGUCAGAGAUUUGCAAAGACUCACGUUUUUGUUGUUUUCUCAUCAUUCCAUUGUGAUACUAAGAAACUAAGAAGCUUAAUGAAAAGAAAUAAAAUGCCUAUGUUGUUGUUCUAGAAA